GGGGCGCUGGGAGCCCGUUGGGCCGCGAACGCAGCCGCCACGCUGGGGCCGCCGAGAUCGGGUGCCCGGGAUGAGCCUCAUCCGGAAAAAGGGCUUCUACAAGCAGGACGUCAACAAGACAGCCUGGGAGCUGCCCAAGACCUACGUGUCCCCGACGCACGUCGGCAGCGGGGCCUAUGGCUCCGUGUGCUCGGCCAUCGACAAGCGGUCAGGGGAGAAGGUGGCCAUCAAGAAGCUGAGCCGACCCUUUCAGUCCGAGAUCUUCGCCAAGCGCGCCUACCGGGAGCUGCUGCUGCUGAAGCACAUGCAGCAUGAGAACGUCAUUGGGCUCCUGGAUGUCUUCACCCCAGCCUCCUCCCUGCGCAACUUCUAUGACUUCUACCUGGUGAUGCCCUUCAUGCAGACGGAUCUGCAGAAGAUCAUGGGGAUGGAGUUCAGUGAGGAGAAGAUCCAGUACCUGGUGUAUCAGAUGCUCAAAGGCCUUAAGUACAUCCACUCUGCUGGGGUCGUGCACAGGGACCUGAAGCCAGGCAACCUGGCUGUGAAUGAGGACUGUGAACUGAAGAUUCUGGAUUUUGGGCUGGCGCGACAUGCAGACGCCGAGAUGACUGGCUACGUGGUGACCCGCUGGUACCGAGCCCCCGAGGUGAUCCUCAGCUGGAUGCACUACAACCAGACAGUGGACAUCUGGUCUGUGGGCUGUAUCAUGGCAGAGAUGCUGACAGGGAAAACUCUGUUCAAGGGGAAAGAUUACCUGGACCAGCUGACCCAGAUCCUGAAAGUGACCGGGGUGCCUGGCACGGAGUUUGUGCAGAAGCUGAACGACAAAGCGGCCAAAUCCUACAUCCAGUCCCUGCCACAGACCCCCAGGAAGGAUUUCACUCAGCUGUUCCCACGGGCCAGCCCCCAGGCUGCGGACCUGCUGGAGAAGAUGCUGGAGCUAGACGUGGACAAGCGCCUGACGGCCGCGCAGGCCCUCACCCAUCCCUUCUUUGAACCCUUCCGGGACCCUGAGGAAGAGACGGAGGCCCAGCAGCCGUUUGAUGAUUCCUUAGAACACGAGAAACUCACAGUGGAUGAAUGGAAGCAGCACAUCUACAAGGAGAUUGUGAACUUCAGCCCCAUUGCCCGGAAGGACUCACGGCGCCGGAGUGGCAUGAAGCUGUAGGGACUCAUCUUGCAUGGCACCGCCGGCCAGACACUGCCCAAGGACCAGUAUUUGUCACUACCAAACUCAGCCCUUCUUGGAAUACAGCCUUUCAAGCAGAGGACAGAAGGGUCCUUCUCCUUAUGUGGGAAAUGGGCCUAGUAGAUGCAGAAUUCAAAGAUGUCGGUUGGGAGAAACUAGCUCUGAUCCUAACAGGCCACGUUAAACUGCCCAUCUGGAGAAUCGCCUGCAGGUGGGGCCCUUUCCUUCCCGCCAGAGUGGGGCUGAGUGGGCGCUGAGCCAGGCCGGGGGCCUAUGGCAGUGAUGCUGUGUUGGUUUCCUAGGGAUGCUCUAACGAAUUACCACAAACCUGGUGGAUUGAAACAGCAGAACUUGAUUCCCUUACAGUUCUGGAGGCUGGAAAUCUGGGAUGGAGGUGUUGGCAGGGCUGUGGUCCCUUUGAAGGCUCUGGGGAAGAAUCCUUCCUUGGCUCUUUUUAGCUUGUGGCGGCAGUGGGCAGUCCGUGGCAUUCCCCAGCUUAUUGCUGCAUCACUCCAGUCUCUGUCUCUUCUGUUCUCUCCUCUUUUAACAACAGUCAUUGGAUUUAGGGCCCACCCUAAUCCUGUGUGAUCUUAUCUUGAUCCUUAUUAAUUAAACCUGCAAAUACUCUAGUUCCAAAUAAAGUCACAUUCUCAGGUUCCAGGUGGACAUGAAUUCCAGGGGGAAAUGAUUCAACUCACUACAGACAGCUGGGAGGGAGGGGCCCCUUCCUGGGCCCCGUGCUGAGGCCUUGUGCUCUGUGAAGGAACCCAAUGUGUUUGGCUGCUAAAUUAAGGGAGUUGCAGAGAGAGCUGCAGCUGGUGCGAUUGCAUUCAGGUUAUUUUGGGUGAGUGAUAAGCAAUCAAGAUAUGAAACAACAGCAGGCUCGGAGACUGCGAGCUGCACAGGCAGAAAUGGGCUCUUGCCUGGCUUGAUGGCAAACCGUUCUGCUCCCUUUGGGAGAUGGCACAGCUCUCCAGAGCUUUGACCUGACAGUGGCUAGAACCUCUCUGUUUUUAUCUGAGAAACUUUGGCAGAACAAAUUUCCAUGUGCACAAGCUGUCGGGCACAGUGGGUCUCAAAUUUCCUUGUGCACCAGGGGACUUGUUAAAAUGCAGAUUCCUGGGCCCCACCCCAGGGCUUGUGACUCAGCAGGUCUGCAGUUGAGACCUUAGAAUGUGCAUUUGAAUGAGGACCUCUCGCCCUGACCCAAGCCUAGUGAUUCUGAUGGAUAUCAGACCAUAGUUCGAGACAUUUAGUGGAUUUCAGUCAUACUUGAUUUGUUGGGAGGCCUAAAUCAAAAACCUAUAGGAGGAGACUGGGGGGCUUCAGAUGGAGUUUCACACUCAUCUUACAGGUGUUAAAACUGAGGCUCAGAAAGCUUUUUUUUGUUUGUUUGUUUGAGACAGGGUCUGGCUCUGUCACCCGGGCUGGAGUUCAGUGGCACAAUUACAUCUUACUGCAACCUCAGCCUCCUGGGCUCAAGCCAUCCUCCCACCUCAGCCUCCUAAGUAGCUGGGACUACAGGUCUGUGCCACCCAGGUGCACCAGGACUGCAGGUGGCUAAUUAAAACAUUUUUUUUCUUUUUUGUAUAGGCGGGGUUUCUCUAUGUUGCCCAGGCUGAUCUUGAACUUCUGGACUCAAGUGAUCCUCCCACUUUGGCCUCCCAAAGUGCUGGGAUUAUAGGCAUGAGCCACCCUGCAGGCCCAGACAGCAUUUUUAAGGCCUUGAAACUCUUCUGUAUAAUACUGUAAUGGUGGAUACCUAUUGUGCAUUUGUUACCAUCUGUAGGACUGGAUAACACAGAGUGAACCCUCAAGUAAACUAUGGACUUCAGUUAAUAAUAAUGUAUCAGUAUUGGUUCAUAAAUUGUAACAAUUGUGCCACACUAAUGCAAGAUGUUACUCAUCAAGAAAACUGAGGAGAGAGAAGGGGAGGAAGUAGGUGGGAACCUCUAUACUUUCUACCAACCUAAAACUGCUCUAAAAAAUAAACCACAGGCCGGUCGCAGUAGCUCACGCCUGUAAUCCCAGCACCUUGGGAGGCUGAGGUGGGCGGAUCACUUGAGGUCAGGAGUUCAAGACCAGCCUGGCCAACAUGGUGAAACCCCAUCUCUACCAAAAAUACAAAAAUUAGCUGGGCUUGGUGGUGCAUGCCUGUAAUCCCAAACUACUCGGGAGGCUGAGGCAGAAUUGCUUGAACCUGGGAGGUGGAGGUUGCAGUGAGCUGAGAUCACACCACUGCACUCCAGCCUGGGUGACAGAGUGAGACUCCAUCUCAAAAAAACAAAAAAAACAAAUACCCUGAGGACACAGAGACAUUGGGUCAGACACCCACAGCUAGGAAGUGGUGGAGUCAGAUUGGAACCCAAGUAGGCUUGAGCACUGUACCCAGCUUGGAUUCAAGGGUUGCCCAGCCUUCCCUCUUCACGCCAGUCUGAGACCCUUACUGCUGACUGUGUCCAUGGUCUCUGUUUUCUCUCCCACAGAAUGGCCCUGCUGUCAAGGAGCUGGGGAGUCCUUGACUGGGACUGGCUAGUCUUGCCACAGCCCUGGCCUCGCUGGUUACUAAAACUGCCCCAGGUUCCCUGAGUCUACAUCCCUCUAAGCCUCCUGAGAAUUCUCACUGCCCCAAGGAAAAAGUCUAGCCUUCCUUCUUGGCCUGGCAUUCAAAACCCCUUGUGUUCUCUCUAAUCUCAUCAGCUCCCACUGCCUCCCCUAGCUAGUCCUUAUGUCAGUGUGGGACACCAGUCCUGGGAUCCACCGUAAGGUUCAUUCUGCAUUCACAGGUUAAAGGUCUUGACAAGUCCUGCAGUAAAGAGAUCCGUUCCUCAUUUAAUCCAGAACUUCCCAGAUGUACUUAACCGCAGGACCCAUUUUCUCCCAACAGCAUGACACACAUAGCCUUUUUUGCCCAGUGCAGCCCAGUGCACAGGUCCCGAUAUUGCCUCUCCCCAAGUAGGCUUGGCCUUCUUUUAGUGCCCGUGCGUGGAAGGCCCUCCAUUCUCCUCUCCAUUCUCCUUGGCCUUCAAGGCUCUACCUUAGGCCUCCCUCCAGGCAGCUGUUCUCCAUCAUCCCCCCUGGGCUGCAGGCCCUCUGUGGGCAGCAUUUAGUGUGUGGUUUGGCCUCCCCUUCCCAUUGCCCACUGUGAGCAAAUACCUGUGCGUGAAUGAAUAAUGAGUGAAAGAUGUCCCAGGGGCCUGUCGGUCACUUCUUUGCCCCGACCAGGCCAAUGUCAUAUGGAAGGUGGCAGAGAGCCCAGCAGGAAGCAGAAGUGGGCGGCCCUGGGCUGUACCUUUGAGCUGCUCUCCUGAAAAUCUCUAUUAUUUCAGACUCCCAGACCCCACCCCCCGCUUCAUCCUCUGGUGUCCUCCUAGGCCAUCCCCACUCCGGAAUUAAACCUCAGCCCCUCCCACAGAGUUUUCUCAAAUCUGUGAAGUUUCUUCAAAAGGCGGUGGAGGUGCUCAGCAGUGCAAGGUGGGGGGUGGAGGGGGUGGGGAGUAGAGGGAGUGGGGGUUCCACGGGUUUGGGUCUUGCCCAGUGGGCACAUGGCCUGUGUAAUAGGAAACAAGUCCAUUCUCCUGCUGUGGGGGGCAGAGGAGCUGGCGGGGCGAGGGAGGGGGAGAUGUGGGCUCAGGUAUUCUUGGUGGAUGCGCUUCGUUCUGUGGCUGAUGGGGUGGCUUAAAAGAUCUUAACAGAGAGAGAUCAGGAAGCCAGACUGCAAGGUGGGGGACAUUUCCUAAGAGCAAGUGUACCCUCCAUUCCCUCUUUUGAGGAACAAAGAGUAUCUUUGCUGGGGCCUGAGUCAUCCAUGAAAACAGACAGCAGCGGUGUCCCAGGGCAGGGCUUGCCUGGCGUGGAUUGGGGUGGUGCUGCCCCCAGUGAGGGGCAGCACAAGGGGAGACAGAAAUGGAGGAAUAGCCCCCGUAAGGGCAAGCCCAGUGUGCACCAGUGCCCAGAGCUGCCUGAUGGAGGAACAGCUCCGUAAGGGUGAACCCAGUGUGCACGGGUGCCCGGAGCUGCCUGCGUGAGGCUGGGGGCUAGUUUGGAUGAGGGCAUGGCUCAACUUUCACUUGGCACAUUGAAAUAGCUUUUGCUGUCUGCUAGGGUGUGGAAAACUGUUUUUCCAUGGCCCCAAGCAAUGCUAUAGCUACAGCUGAGGAGGGAGGAAUCUCUCCCUGCCUCUCCUCCCAACUCUUGGCUUUUGCUUCCUUAAAUUUGAACAAUUCCCUAAGAUCUAAUGCUGGGAGGCUCCCCUUCCUUCAUUACACAGUGAACUCAUGUGCUCUAUCUGCAUUCCCCCUAAAUCCUCCUGAGCUUUUAGGUAAGAGGCCGAUGAUUUCACAAUCGGCAGCAGAGGCCUAAGGCCAUUCCAUCAAACUGAAGAUGGCAGCAAGUUGUCCUCACUUCUUCAUUGAGCACCCAUGGGUGUGUACUGGAGCAAGGGUGGUGCCAGGGAUUCUCCUGCUCUGGUUCCUCCUGCGGGGUCCCUGCUCAGCUGGGCAGCUGCCCUCACUCUGGGCGGGUGGCAUGUGAGUGUCAACAGGGCCCCUCUCAGUCAGGGGCUCUUGGCCAUUUUUUGUGCCAUGGAUCGCUUCUCAAAAUCAUAUUUUCUUUUCUUUUCUUUUGAGAUGGGGUCUCACUCCAUUACCCAGGCUGGAGUGCAGUGGUGCAAUCACAGCUCACUGUAGCCUCGACCUCCCUGGGUUCAGGUGAUCCUCCCACCUCAGCCUCCCAAGUAGCUGGGACUAUAGGCAUGCACCACCAUGCCUGGCUAAUUUCAGAAUAAUAUUUUCAUACACAUAAAAUAUGUAGGAUUACAAAGUAAGCUAGUUAUAUUUAUAUACAGUUGUCAAAAUAUUUUUAAAAUGUAUAACGUGAUACUAUGUGUAUAGGUUUCUUUAUUAACAUAUUGAAUAAAAAGAUCGAGGGUAGGCCUAUUAAACAAUGGUAAACUGAAGAGAGAUGAGUGUAAACAAUAUUUUAAGAUAGAUACCUGUGGCAAACUGUAAAGGGAUAUGAAAAACUCUGUAAUUUCUAUUGGCACUGCUGAUACAACUGCACUUUGCUACCUUUGUUCAUAACCAAGGAAAUAGAAAUGACUGAAAAUAAAGUUGUAUUCUAUUCCAA